GAUGUCACCGCGCGGCUGCGACGGCCCAGGAGCGCGUCUCGGCGGGAGCCUCAGGUACGCGGCGGGGGCGGGGGAGCGGGAAGCGGGCGGCUGGGUCCGCUUCCCCCGGGAGGCCGGCGGGGCUGCGGGCGGACGGGGGUGAAGAGCGGGCGGCGAGGCGGUGGUCGCGGGGCAGCCCGGGCAUCGUUCGGCCGGGACGUGUCUGGCUCGGCGCCGCGUCAGGUUGCGCCAGUGGAGUCGGACCCCAGCGCGCCUCUCCCAGCUGCAGAGCUGCAGGGCGGAGAGGCGGCCCACUCUAAGCUGGCGGCGCGGCUCAGGGGCGCGGCUGGGCGCGCCGCGUGUGGCGCCGGCGGGCAGCGCGGUCUCACUCCGCCACCCUCCGCUCCUGCCCUUUGUCGCCAAGCAUCUGGAGAAGCCGGGUCCUUCCCUCCCGGGCUCGCGCUGUCCCCUGCGCGCGAUCCUUCCCCGACGGUGAACCCAACGGGAAAGGCCCAGAACUGCGCGGGGCUGCGGCCAUCUGCUGUCGAGCCGCUCCGCGUGUCUCUGCCGCCCCCUGCGGCCGCCGGGGCCUGCGCCUCUCUCCCUCCCGUGCCUCGGCUCCCAGAGAUUGAACCCCAGGUAACCGGGUCUGUCCACGCCCGCGGCCGCCUCUCCCCGGGUGUCGCCAGCUUCCUGCAUUUCCUGUGCAUGGCACGGAGCUCGGGUCUCCAGAGACUCUGCAUCUGGGGUGCAGCGACCGAUGAGCCCGUAAACCAGUCGCACACUCGGAGCGUGGAUGCUGCGUGGGGUGCGCUGUCAGCGCGGACAGGCUGGGAGAACGGGGGACGCUGGGGACAGGGAGAGCCGGUGAACUUCCCAGAACGUCCGCCUAGCCAGACCCAGCUGCGGGUACUGGGUUUUGAGACGUGGUCCAGUACCCAGGAACUCAGUCUGACAGGGAGACAGCGCCUACACAGUGAGCCCAGUACUGAGGGAAGACCCGCUGGGAGGGGCGGCCUGGAUAGCCCCUCCACAGAGAGGUCAGAUGUGAGGUGGCCUUGAGGGAGGUAUGAUGUAAAUCCUGAUCAUUCGUUGUAUUUGAGGCUGUCCGUUCUCCUGUGCCUCCUCGGUCGCCUUACUUGGAUCUGUUCCCAUUGCCUUGGUGUGAUUUUAUCCACCGGAAACUGUCUUCAGCUAUUUCCCCAGUAACCUCUAACUAAAAACCUGGGUCUUGCCUGGUCUACCCUCCCCUGCUGAACUCCAGAGCCACAUCCCAACUGCUGCCUGACUUGUCACAGACACCAUGAAGCCCAGACUGAAGGAGCACUGGCCCCCUUGACAAUUCCUCAGCCCCAGCUCCUCCUUUCAGACUGGUGCCUCCACCUGCCAGACCCCUAGCUUUGAAGGCCAAUCUCAUCUUCGUCUCCUUCCUCUCUGGCUCCUUCAUUCAGGUGACAAGUAUACAUCAAAUGCCCACCCCAACUCCCCCUCCCAGGACUCCAAUCUGGUGUCUUUCUAGCGGGGAGUCUAGGUUGCUCCCUCUGCUCUGGAGAGGCUUGGCAAAAUGCCUGCAGAGCUCCUUGAGCUCCACCUCUGAACUCCCUUUCAGCAGCCGGCACAGGCAUAACAGCCCAGCCCACAGGUACCACUGCCACUGAGGCAGGGACCCCUAAGGUAGGGCUACCCCCAGCCACAGGGGCUGGCUGGACUGCAAGAGGCUCCCUGCAGCCAGACAAGUAUGAAAAUGCCUUGUUGUUUUGUGCUGAGGCCCCCCAAAACACACCAAAGCAGCUGGGCCCUCUUGGCAUGGUAGGUUCUGCAAAGCACCCACUGUGAGGAGCCUGCGUGAACAUCAACCUGAUAGGGCCACCAGUGCAAAAGCAUCUUCAACAAGUUACAGUCAAUAAGGAAACACAUGUGUAGACACAUUUUUAUUGCCCAUUCAAGCUGUUUUUAUUUGCUGAAUUCAGAAUCCUUUAACAUAGUAACUCACAAAUAAGAUAGAUUUUCAUAGAUUUUCAAGACCUCUUUUGAGGAAACAUCUUGUGUUUGGUGAUCCCCAUCUGUAGCUGCAGCAAGCCAAAAUGGGCAGGAUGGGUGACAUGAGCUAGUGCUCCCAAGCUGGACUCAGAAAGAGUAGGAAGAGAAAGGGCUAAUGUCUGAGCAGUCGGGUGGGCUUCCUAGAUGAGGGGACUGUCCUCCCAGGAGCUGCUACUCAGAGUAGUUUCUUGUCCUCCUAAAGUUUAGAGUGGAAAUACUUUGCAAAAGAGGUCCCCAACCCUAAGUGUGAGGGCUAAGCUCCUGGGCUUAGUAGGCAUAUACAAAUGCCCCCAGGUGGGUGACAUCAAGAUGUUCUGGUCCUAGGUCUGCUGAGAGCCUCUCCUGGGAAUGUUGUAGGCACACCCACUCAACUCUUACCCUUGAUCCCCCUCCCAGGACCAGAAGGGAUUGAUUUCUGGUGAGUCCUGCCCCAAGCUGUGCUUGCCUGCUCUGUUCGUACCUAAUAUUGCAUGAGGAACCUGGCCAGUGUCUAUGGUGGCAAGUGCUUCACCCAUUCUGUCCUCUUCCCCAGAAAAGACUAAUAGGGAGGGAAGAAGCGUGCGCAGAAGCUAAGGAACUCUCUUCCUUCUCUACCAAGGCCACCCCUACAUCUACUCCCUGCAAAUCUGUUAUUUCCCUUGACAUUCAGCAAAUAUUUGGGGUUUUGUUUUGUUUUGUUUUGUUUUGUUUUGUUUUGAGACAGAGCCUCACUUUGUCGCCAGGCUGGAGUGCAGUGGCGCGAUCUCGGCUCACUACAACUUCCGCCUCCCGGGUUCAAGCGAUUCUUCUGCCUCAGCCUCCCGAGUAGCUGGGACUACAGGCGUGUGCCACCACGCCCAGCUAAUUUUUGGUAUUUUUAGUAGAGAUGGGGUUUCACGAUGUUGGCCAGGAUGCUCUUGAUCUCUUUACCUAGUGAUCCGCCCACCUCGGCCUCCCAAAGUGCUGGGAUUACAGGCGUGAGCCACUGCACCCGGCCCAAAUAUUUAACAUUGACUGUAUGCCAGGGACUCUGCUGGGCACUGAGAGUGCAGCAAUGAGGAAGAGCAGGGCCCAUUCUCAGGAAGCUCAGGGGUGGGAAUGGGAGGAGGGAAUCAGAAGCAAGCCAACAGGGACAGUGUGGGGUGGGGGUCAGCUCAGCACACUGUAGGAGUCCCAAAAAGUGAGGAGACCUCUAAGCUGAGUCCUACAGGAGAAGCAAGAAUAGAAGCAGGGCAAAGAUGGGGGUCGGCCCAUCAUUCCUAGACGAAAGGCAGAGUUUGAGAAGUGGGGGCCAGAUUAUUUUGGAAUCUGCCAAUAGUGUAUGGGGAGGUAGGGGUGACUUUCCCAUAGUGGAGUGUGGGCUUCCUUGGAGGAUUCAGGCUGUUGGGGAACAGGAGGGAUGGUAAACUGCCUUUCAGCAGGGCUUGCUUCUAGGAAAUUGAUUCUGGCUGCAGUGAGCGUGGAGGCAGGCCUGGAUUCCAGGCAGGCUUCUGCCACGUCCCAGCUGUGUGGCCCUGGACAAAUCAUUUCCCUCUCAGAACCUCAUUGUCCUUGUCUGUAAAAUGCAGACAGCAGUUGCAACGAUCAAAAUAAAUAUUUAUAUAAAGCACCUGGAACAUAACAGGCACAGAGGGAGGGAGGAAGGCUGUGAAGCUGCCUCUGCCCCUUGCCCUGGGUCUUCCCCCACCCCUCCUUUCUUAGCUCCCCUGAGGUCACAAGAGUGUUCUUGACCAUUGUUUAUCAGGGAAAGAUCACAUGGAGAAGCCAACAGAACGGCCAGGAAGCAGCCUGGGUGGAACAGGGUUGGGGAGGAAAGGAACAUGGGUACAUUCUCAGCGUUCCAGGAGGUCUCAGGGUAAAGGCUGCUUGUGUGGGCAAGGGGAGCCUGGCAGGGAAUGAGCUGGUCCCAAUUCCUUCCCCUGAGCUGGGCCCUCAACCUUCAGAGGUGCUCCCUGGGACUGGUCCUACUUCCUCUGCCACCUCUGAUCCCAAGGUGACUCUGCCAAAAUCUGGGGGAUGCCAGCGCUUGUGACGGUGUGACCAGGGAGGGGAAGUGACCCACGCAGCCACCCAGCCUCAGCACUCAUCUGCGCAGCCAUGGAGGCCCUGGGACCUGGGGGCGACCGCGCCUCCCCGGCCUCGUCCACUAGCAGCCUGGACCUGUGGCAUCUGUCCAUGCGCGCGGACUCGGCCUACAGCUCUUUCUCCGCAGCCUCCGGCGGCCCCGAGCCGCGCACGCAGUCGCCGGGGACAGACCUCCUUCCUUACCUAGACUGGGACUACGUGCGUGUGGUUUGGGGCGGCCCGGGCCCCGCCCCGCCCGACGCUGCCCUUUGCACAUCCCCGCGGCCCCGGCCCGCGGUUGCAGCCCGCAGUGGGCCGCAGCCAACAGAGGUCCCGGGGACCCCGGGACCACUGAACAGGCAGGCCACCCCGCUGCUGUACGCGCUGGCGGCCGAGGCGGAGGCCGCGGCGCAGGCUGCCGAGCCGCCCAGCCCGCCGGCCUCGAGGGCCGCCUACCGCCAGCGGCUUCAGGGCGCGCAGCGGCGAGUGCUCCGGGAGACGUCGUUCCAGCGCAAGGAGCUCCGCAUGAGCCUGCCCGCCCGUCUGCGGCCCACUGUCCCAGCGCGGCCCCCGGCGACUCACCCGCGCUCCGCCUCGCUCAGCCACCCGGGCGGGGAGGGGGAGCCGGCGCGCUCCCGGGCUCCCGCGCCAGGAACUGCCGGCCGGGGUCCCCUCGCCAACCAGCAGCGGAAGUGGUGCUUCUCAGAGCCAGGAAAGCUGGAUCGUGUGGGUCGGGGCGGUGGGCCGGCGCGGGAAUGCCUGGGUGAGGCCUGCUCCAGCUCUGGCCUCCCUGGGCCCGAGCCCUUGGAGUUCCAGCAUCCGGCGCUGGCUAAGUUUGAAGAUCACGAGGUCGGAUGGCUGCCCGAGACGCAACCCCAAGGCUCCAUGAACCUGGACUCCGGGUCCUUGAAGCUCGGUGAUGCCUUCAGGCCCGCCAGUCGGAGUCGGAGCGCUUCAGGCGAAGUCUUGGGUUCCUGGGGAGGAUCAGGAGGGACCAUACCCAUUGUCCAGGCUGUUCCCCAAGGAGCAGAAACCCCCAGACCAUUGUUUCAGACCAAACUUUCCAGGUUCUUGCCUCAGAAAGAGGCUGCGGUGAUGUAUCCUGCAGAGUUACCCCAGAGCAGCCCUGCUGACAGUGAACAGAGGGUCUCAGAGACCUGCAUUGUGCCUGCCUGGCUCCCCUCCCUUCCUGAUGAAGUGUUCCUAGAAGAGGCCCCACUGGUCAGAAUGAGAUCACCACCAGACCCCCAUGCCUCCCAGGGGCCCCCAGCCAGUGUCCAUGCCUCUGACCAGCCGUAUGGAACUGGCUUAGGCCAAAGAACUGGCCAGGUUACAGUCCCCACAGAGUACCCGCUCCAUGAGUGUCCAGGAACUGCAGGGGCAGAUGACUGCUGGCAGGGGGUGAAUGGUUCUGUAGGUAUUUCCAGGCCCACAAGCCACACCCCCACUGGGACUGCAAAUGAUAACAUCCCAACUAUUGACCCCACUGGACUGACCACCAAUCCCCCCACAGCUGCAGAGAGUGACCUCCUCAAACCUGUCCCAGCUGAUGCCUUGGGACUUUCAGGCAAUGAUACUCCAGGUCCCUCUCACAAUACUGCCCUAGCCAGGGGCACUGGCCAGCCUGGUUCCAGGCCCACAUGGCCUAGUCAGUGCCUCGAGGAGCUGGUUCAGGAGCUGGCCAGAUUAGAUCCCUCUCUAUGUGACCCUCUUGCUUCCCAGCCCAGCCCAGAGCCACCCCUGGGCCUGCUGGAUGGACUGAUUCCUUUAGCAGAGGUCCGGGCUGCAAUGCGGCCUGCCUGUGGGGAGGCUGGAGAGGAGGCUGCCAGUACUUUUGAGCCAGGGUCCUAUCAGUUCAGCUUCACCCAGCUCCUGCCGGCUCCUCGGGAGGAGACAAGGCUUGAAAACCCUGCCACCCACCCUGUGCUUGACCAGCCAUGUGGGCAGGGGCUCCCUGCACCAAACAACAGCAUCCAGGGCAAGAAAGUGGAGCUGGCCGCCCGCCUCCAAAAGAUGCUUCAGGACCUUCACACGGAGCAGGAGCGGCUGCAGGGGGAGGCACAAGCGUGGGCCAGGCGCCAAGCGGCUCUGGAGGCUGCAGUGCGCCAGGCCUGUGCCCCUCAGGAGCUGGAGCGGUUCAGCCGGUUCAUGGCCGACCUAGAGCGCGUGCUUGGCCUUCUGCUGCUGCUGGGCAGUCGCCUGGCGCGCGUGCGCCGCGCCCUGGCCCGGGCGGCCUCAGACAGCGACCCUGAUGAGCAGGCCUCCCUGCUGCAGCGACUCCGGCUCCUGCAGCGGCAGGAGGAGGACGCCAAGGAGCUGAAGGAGCACGUAGCGCGGCGCGAGCGGGCCGUGCGGGAGGUGCUGGUGCGAGCACUACCGGUGGAGGAGCUGCGCGUCUAUUGCGCCCUGCUGGCGGGCAAGGCCGCCGUCCUGGCCCAGCAGCGCAACCUGGACGAGCGCAUCCGCCUCCUUCAGGACCAACUGGACGCCAUCAGGGACGACCUUGGCCAUCAUGCCCCGUCUCCCAGCCCGGCGCGGCCCCCAGGGACCUGUCCUCCAGUUCAGCCGCCCUUCCCUCUUCUCCUUACAUAGUUAUAGGUGGAGAGGGUGGGGUGCACCGCCCCUAUCUCUCACCCACGUAAGUGGGGUGAUGCUGAUUUAGUCUCUGCUUUUCCCUUGAGGGAUUGGGGAGGACCCAGUCCAGGCCUUUCUAAGAUACUCCUCCAGCCGGGCGCGGUGGCUCACGCCUGUAAUCCCAGCACUUUGGGAGGCCGAGGCGGGCGGAUCACAAGGUCAGGAGAUCGAGACCAUCCUGGCUAACACGGUGAAACCCCGUCUCUACUAAAAAUAUAAAAAAUUAGCCGGGCGUGGUGGCGGGUGCCUGUAUUGCCAGCUACUCGGAAGGCUGAGGCAGGAGAAUGGCGUGAACCUGGGAGGUGGAGCUUGCAGUGAGCGGACAUCGCGCCACUGCACUCCAGCCUGGGCGACAGAGCAAGACUCCGUCUCAAAAAAAAAAAAAAAAAAAAAAAAAAAAAAGAUACUUCUCCAAAGUGUUCUCAUGUGGCCUCACCCAGGUCUUGUGUAUUAUUUGGUAAUUAAUUUAUGGAUCUUAAAAACUGCAGUAUUCCCCCAUUUUGUGAUGAGAGUGUGGGGCUGGCAGGGGUUGGUUGGAGGGAGGAGAGAAGACAGAGGAGCACUUAAGGUGCAAAGCAGCCUAUUUUUUCUUCAAUAAAAAUUGUUAAGAGAA